GUAGAGCAGAGCAGAAGCCUGAGCCAGACGGAGAGCCACCUCCUCUCCCAGGAACUGAACCCAAAGGAUCACCUGGUAUUCCCUGAGAGUACAGAUUUCUCCGGCGUGGCCCUCAAGGGACAGACAUGGCUCAGCGGAUGACAACACAGCUGCUGCUCCUUCUAGUGUGGGUGGCUGUAGUAGGGGAGGCUCAGACAAGGAUUGCAUGGGCCAGGACUGAGCUUCUCAAUGUCUGCAUGAACGCCAAGCACCACAAGGAAAAGCCAGGCCCCGAGGACAAGUUGCAUGAGCAGUGUCGACCCUGGAGGAAGAAUGCCUGCUGUUCUACCAACACCAGCCAGGAAGCCCAUAAGGAUGUUUCCUACCUAUAUAGAUUCAACUGGAACCACUGUGGAGAGAUGGCACCUGCCUGCAAACGGCAUUUCAUCCAGGACACCUGCCUCUACGAGUGCUCCCCCAACUUGGGGCCCUGGAUCCAGCAGGUGGAUCAGAGCUGGCGCAAAGAGCGGGUACUGAACGUGCCCCUGUGCAAAGAGGACUGUGAGCAAUGGUGGGAAGAUUGUCGCACCUCCUACACCUGCAAGAGCAACUGGCACAAGGGCUGGAACUGGACUUCAGGGUUUAACAAGUGCGCAGUGGGAGCUGCCUGCCAACCUUUCCAUUUCUACUUCCCCACACCCACUGUUCUGUGCAAUGAAAUCUGGACUCACUCCUACAAGGUCAGCAACUACAGCCGAGGGAGUGGCCGCUGCAUCCAGAUGUGGUUCGACCCAGCCCAGGGCAACCCCAAUGAGGAGGUGGCGAGGUUCUAUGCUGCAGCCAUGAGUGGGGCUGGGCCCUGGGCAGCCUGGCCUUUCCUGCUUAGCCUGGCCCUAAUGCUGCUGUGGCUGCUCAGCUGACCUCCUUUUACCUUCUGAUACCUGGAAAUCCCUGCCCUGUUCAGCCCCACAGCUCCCAACUAUUUGGUUCCUGCUCCAUGGUCGGGCCUCUGACAGCCACUUUGAAUAAACCAGACACCGCA